ACAGGCGGCGCGGGCAGCGCGAGCCCCGGAGCCCCGGAGGCCUGUGCGCCCUGAGCCGGCAUGGACCCCGAGCACUGCGCGCCUUUCCGCGUGGGGCCUGCACCCGGCCCCUAUGUGGCCUCGGGGGACGAGCCUCCGGGCCCGCAGGGAACCCCCGCCGCUGCGCCUCACCUGCACCCCGCGCCGCCCCGCGGCCCGCGGCUGACCCGCUUUCCGGCCUGCGGGCCCCUGGAGCCCUACCUCCCAGAGCCGGCCAAGCCGCCCGCCAAGUACCUGCAGGACCUCGGGCCCGGCCCGGCCCUCAACGGCGGCCACUUCUACGAGGGCCCCGCGGAAGCUGAGGAGAAGACCUCCAAAGCUGCCAGCUUCCCCCAGCUGCCCUUGGACUGCCGAGGGGGCCCCAGAGACGGGCCCUCUAACUUGCAAGGCUCCCCAGGCCCCUGCCUGGCCAGCCUGCAUCUUCCUCUUUCCCCGGGACUCCCUGACUCCAUGGAGUUGGCCAAGAACAAGAGCAAGAAGCGUCGUAACCGCACGACCUUCAGCACAUUCCAGCUGGAGGAGCUGGAGAAGGUCUUCCAGAAAACCCACUAUCCUGAUGUGUAUGCCCGGGAGCAGCUGGCCCUGCGCACAGACCUGACUGAGGCCCGGGUACAGGUCUGGUUCCAGAACCGCAGAGCCAAGUGGCGGAAGCGCGAGCGUUAUGGGAAGAUCCAGGAGGGGCGGAACCCCUUCACGGCUGCCUAUGACAUCUCUGUGCUGCCCCGUACUGACAGCCACCCUCAGCUGCAGAACUCCCUGUGGGCCAGUCCAGGAUCUGGGAGCCCUGGAGGCCCCUGCCUUGUGUCUCCAGAGGGCAUCCCCUCCCCAUGCAUGUCUCCAUAUUCCCACCCCCAUGGGAGUGUGGCUGGCUUCAUGGGGGUGCCAGCCCCUUCUGCGGCUCACCCUGGCAUCUACUCCAUCCAUGGCUUUCCCCCCACCCUGGGGGGCCACAGCUUUGAGCCUUCCUCAGAUGGUGACUAUAAGUCUCCAAGCCUCGUCUCGCUCAGGGUAAAGCCCAAGGAGCCACCCGGCCUUCUGAACUGGACCACGUGAUCGGUUGCAUGGACCUGCAGAAUGAGCUGCCCACCUCUUUUUCCAUUCCCAGUCGCUCCCAGCCCACCUCUGCCUCCAAGCCCCAGAUGGUUCUGGAGGCUGCGAGAGCAGCUGGCACUGUCAGCCCCCAGCAGGGAACACGUUACAGGGUCUUUUCUCUUAGAACAAGGUGGGGCUGCCUAGGAGAAGGGGCUUCGAAGCAGCCAGGACUCUUCCUACCACAAACUGAGUCCCCUCACCUGAACUCUGGGCUGGAGGCAGGGAGACACUGCCCUGCUUCCUCCAGACUUUGUCCAAGUCCAUUGUCAUCUCUCCAGCUAAGACAGCUUACUUGGCUCAUCGUUCAGGGAACCCAGGAAAAUGGGAGGAGAACGCCGCGUGGACUGAAGCUCUUCAUGAUGAGAUGGAAACCAAAAGGGAGUCUCCCAUGAUGGGGUGGAGUCAGCCCUGCUUCCCCUCCCCACCAGCAGGGGGCGCACUGGUGUCUGACACUAAGGAGGGUGUAAAGGCCAAGGUCAGCAUAGACUGAGGCACACUGGCUCCUCAGCUCCAGCCACCCUCACUCCUGCCAUGUGCCUGCACUCCCAGCAUGCCAUGCAGUCAUCUUCCCCUCCAAGGGGGCAGAAAUUCCACCAGAAAUCACCACAUAUUUGGAAUCUCUUCCACGGGACCAGCCCAGAGCUAUGCCAUGGAAAUGAUAUUGGAUGUUGGUAAGAAUAAAACAGAUUUCUACAGACUGAGAUCCUGAUCCCCAUUUUUGUACAGACACUUUUGUGUUUUUUUUGUUUAAAAAAAAAAAAAAGGAGAGAGAGAGAAAAAAAAGGCUGCCCAGCAUUCUAAUAAAGGUGGUGGUGUUUUUUAUA